AGUGUGCGCCGCGGGUGCUGGGGGCUCGAGAACCGAGCGGAGCUGGUUGAGCCUUCAAAGUCCUAAAACGCGCGGCCGUGGGUUCGGGGUUUAUUGAUUGAAUUCCGCCGGCGCGGGAGCCUCUGCAGAGAGAGAGCGCGAGAGAUGGAGAUGGGCAGACGGAUUCAUUUAGAGCUGCGGAACAGGACGCCCUCUGAUGUGAAAGAACUUGUCCUGGACAACAGUCGGUCGAAUGAAGGCAAACUCGAAGGCCUCACAGAUGAAUUUGAAGAACUGGAAUUCUUAAGUACAAUCAACGUAGGCCUCACCUCAAUCGCAAACUUACCAAAGUUAAACAAACUUAAGAAGCUUGAACUAAGCGAUAACAGAGUCUCAGGGGGCCUGGAAGUAUUGGCAGAAAAGUGUCCGAACCUCACGCAUCUAAAUUUAAGUGGCAACAAAAUUAAAGACCUCAGCACAAUAGAGCCACUGAAAAAGUUAGAAAACCUCAAGAGCUUAGACCUUUUCAAUUGCGAGGUAACCAACCUGAACGACUACCGAGAAAAUGUGUUCAAGCUCCUCCCGCAACUCACAUAUCUCGACGGCUAUGACCGGGACGACAAGGAGGCCCCUGACUCGGAUGCUGAGGGCUACGUGGAGGGCCUGGAUGAUGAGGAGGAGGAUGAGGAUGAGGAGGAGUAUGAUGAAGAUGCUCAGGUAGUGGAAGACGAGGAGGACGAGGAUGAGGAGGAGGAAGGUGAAGAGGAGGACGUGAGUGGAGAGGAGGAGGAGGAUGAAGAAGGUUAUAACGAUGGAGAGGUAGAUGACGAGGAAGAUGAAGAAGAGCUUGGUGAAGAAGAAAGGGGUCAGAAGCGAAAACGAGAACCUGAAGAUGAGGGAGAAGAUGAUGACUAAGUGGAAUAACCUAUUUUGAAAAAUUCCUAUUGUGAUUUGACUGUUUUUACCCAUAUCCCCUCUCCCCCCCCCCUCCAAUCCUGCCCCCUGAAACUUAUUUUUUUCUGAUUGUAACGUUGCUGUGGGAACGAGAGGGGAAGAGUGUACUGGGGGUUGCGGGGGGAGGGAUGGCGGGUGGGGGUGGAAUAAAAUACUAUUUUUACUGCCACUCUUUAUUUUUUUCCCCUACUUUUUCUUUGUGUCCGGUUUUUGUCCCUGUAAAUGCGAUAGCUAAGUACACACUAAGUGAGCAUUUGUUCCUGACUCUCAAAGAGGAUGGUUUGGAGUUCUCUUACGUUUCCUGGUAUUUCCCAAGUCUCUUGGGUUGGUUGGAAGGCUGUGGCUGGUCUCAGUUUGGUUACUCAAUGCCCAGGAGGGGCUGAGCACCAGCCAUAUCUUUUGCUUUGGUUCACAUGAUGAUACCUGCUUUUCUCAGGCCUGCUAGAGGCAUCCAACGCCCUGGUUUGUAAAUAGCAACCUAAAGGCGUAUUUUGGCACUGGUCUGGGGACAUUCCCCAUCUCUCAUCCCUUUUCCCCCUUCACAGAUGGUGGUGGGCUUCGCUCUACAAAGAGGACUCUGAUGUUACUCUUGAGCUUAUGAGCCAGAGAGCUGAAAACCGCAGGCUUGUUGUGUUAAGUUACAAGGAAAAUGGAUUUGGUAAUUAAAAUUAGAAGAAACACACCUUCAAACUUCAACUUCUUUAAAAGAAAAAAAAAACUGUCCUAUCUUGUUCUGUAAAAUAUUAGAACGCUUUGUUUUACAAAAAAUGAUGAGAGAAUUCUUCCACAUGUACUUCUGUGCUUAGAACAUUUUUACGGACCUAAGCGCUGGAGACGUUGCUGCAUGUCGGCUGGGUUUUUUUUUUCAUACACCCGAGCACGGAAAAACUAACGCAAAAUUGUAUUUUCUUACCUAGUGGAAAUCUGAAAUGACUGCAAAUUCCUAGUGAAUGUACAGGUUUGCUUUCGUGUCCCUCUUCUGGUUGCUUUAGAAGUGACGUGUAAUUUCUGAACCCAUGUUUCAUCUGUAUAAAAGAACAUCUGCACCAGUUUUUCUCCUGCCCCUCAGAAGAGCCAAACUUUGAGUUUUAUGUCUGUUUGUCAUUGAUAAAUUUCAAUAAAUCUUUUUAUACAAUUUUUUUGGGGAUGGCUUCUUUGAGUCCAACAGGCCAUUGAUCUUUUCAAGAUGCAUUCCAGAUGAACUGCUAGGUGAGGGGGAAGCUUCAUUUUUGUUACCUGAUAGAAUAGCUUUUCUUAUGAGAUAUAUAUAAUGUGAUACUAUGUUUGGAUAUUUUUGGUCUUAAAGCAAGACUCAGUGGUGUAUCUUCAUUAAAAGCUUCCUUUAAAAAAGUUACAGAGUUACUAAAAAAACAAGUACCCAAACAAUCAAGUUGGGCCAACCUUGGAACCUUGUUUUGAAUAUCUUUCAUUGUUUUGUUUGUCGUAUUGUAAAAAGAAUGUAUGGUUGAAAACUCAGGAAUGUUUAUAAAACAAAUUAUUUCACAAA